GGAAAUGCACAAGCCUCUUGAUGCAUAAAAACAGCUGGGCUCCCUUGGAGACAGAGCGCCAUGGGAAACCGGGUCUGCUGCGGAGGAAGCUGGAGCUGCCCAUCAACUUUCCAGAAGAAAAAGAAAACAGGAAGCCAAACAAGACGGACACUGAAGCCGCAGCCACAACAGCUGCAGCAGAAUCUCCCAAAGGGCCAUGAAACAACAGGACAUACGUAUGAACGGGUGUUACAGCAGCAAGGGUCUCAAGAGAGGAGUCCAGGCCUCAUGUCGGAAGACAGCAACUUACAUUAUGCUGACAUUCAAGUGUGCAGCCGUCCCCAUGCCCGGGAAGUGAAACACGUGCAUUUAGAAAACGCUACAGAGUAUGCGACCCUUCGCUUCCCCCAGGCCACACCUCGCUAUGACAGCAAGAACGGGACCCUGGUGUGAGCGCUUGGGAGGAAGGCCCAGUCCAUCGUUAACCACUACACCUGUGGGGGAGAACCUACUGCUUUGGGGAAUUGGGUGGCAACCCAGGGAUGUUGUCCACGUUUUAAGCUUAAAGAACUCCAAAGCCCCUGGAAUUGUGGGCGUCCCAUUUUCUCCCCUGGCCUCUUACUUGCCACUGUUAGGUUGGAGUUAAUAGUUGGUUUAGCUAUGGGUGGAUAGCUAAACUUAGCUAUCCACAUGAGGUUAGGUGGAGUGUGCAGGGAGGUAGGUCUUCGACCCCACCAUUGUUGCUCCUGCUCUUGCAAAGUGCAGAAAGAGCAGGUAAAAAGUUAGCCCAUAAGCACGUGGGCUGAUCUUGUUGGACUUUAAUUAAUGGUAUCCUUUUUCACACACCUUAAACUCCAAAGCUGAAGGGGAGGUGCUCCGGAAAAGCAUUCUGAGCUUUUACAUUCAGACACUAGGGCUGGCUUGGGCCAUUUCCUCAGUGGCUGAGUCAGGUUCCAGACCUUAACAGACAAAUGGGGGAAGGGGGCUGAGGCGUGGAGGAAACGCUUUCAGGACCUCAAGUCAGUGAUAACCGACAGCACAGUGAGGCCUGGAAACUUCCCUCGGAGGGACUGUUGGCUCUCGCAGGUGCGGGGCCGCUAGGAUCAAUAAACGGCCUGAGAAACA